AAUAUAGAAACUGUCCCUAAGAGAGGAAACCUUUCUGGCCAUGUUAUUCCAGGAAUCUUUUGUCCCCUAAGUUUGACCUUGUUCUUUCGUUCACCCUUUACUCUUGCAUCAGUCACACAUUCAAAUGGUCACUCACUAAAGAAAACAAUUAAAAAACUGUUUGUGAAACUUUAUAUCUUUAAAGUGAAUAGAGAUCAUUCUGCUAUUUUAGAUUUUGCUUUCAGAAUCUUAAGUGCACUAUCAUGGCUUGCACCAUGUUCUGAAGAGUAGUUGGCCAUGAUUUAACUUCUUUUUUUAAUUUUUAAUUUGCGUGAAAAGCAUUUUGGGCAAAAGAGUAAACCGUGCCUUAGUUGUGUUGGUAUUACGGGGACAGUUAGGGUUUACUGUGAUCAACCACCAGAGUUAUGUUUGGUUUAUCUGGGUGAGUAAUGAAUGCCCCACCCUGUUGUAGAUUUGGUGUAGAUUGCAAUAUUCUACCUGUGCUUGACUUUAGAAUAAGACCUGUUCUAAAAUGGGCUGUCUACAUACAGCCUGCUAAAUUUUUGCUUUGAGAUUAUUUUUAGAAUUUUAUGAUACUGCUUUAAAGUAAUCGAAGAUACUCAAGUUUGGAAAGCAAGGAUAGUGCAUUGUUAUUUUAGGCACGUUGGGAAAGUUGUUUUUGAGACUUGUAUGUUAGUUGAUAUUAUUGGUAAAGUUAGAAGGAUAUUGCACACUGCACUUUAUUUACAGUGAAAUAAUUCAAGAUUUAAUAAUGAGAAUUUAAAAGAGUUUCCUUCCUAAUCCUCCCUAUUCUAUUUUGAAUACCUUCAAGUUCAAUUUUUAAAGACUUAAGGCUUAGGAAAGAGCACAUGGUCAUGUGAACGCUAAGCAAUAUUUAAUAUGUAUGGUACCAUUUGUUUAUAAUUGUCUUCAGUGUUGAAUAUUAAAGUCUGUUUCAAAGUGAGAAAUACCAAUUUUUCACUUCCUAAGUUUGAACAAUGGGAAGAACUUUGUAAGUUUAGGAUUUUUUUAUUUUCAUUUGAUUUUGACUAAACUGUAUUAAAUAACUAUGCAGGCUCUAUUGUAUGGUUCAGAGGUUAUGCAUAAAAUUGUAGAAUCAAGAAUCAAGUUAACGAAAGUGAUCUUGGCUGUCGAGUCCAAUUUCCUACUUUAAUGAAUCCCCUCCACACACAAAGGGAGUAGUAGUUAAUUCAAAAUAUUAUCAUUAUGAUGCUACUUUUAGUAUGGCUGUGUUUUAGAUCAUUUCAUUGUUAUUGGGGAUUUUUUUUAGAGAAACUUUUAUACUUCCAUAAUAUUUAGAUUGUUUUACAGAAGAAACACUUAAAUGUGUUUGCUUUCCGUAUUAAUACACGAUUACUUUGUUACUCAUAUUAGAACUAUUUAAAAAUAUUUAUAUGGAUACAAGUAAACCAUCUACCUCGAUAAGUUGACAGAUUUAAAUCCGUCAAGCUAGUAACCAGGAAGCGGACUUAAAGCUGGUAACUAGGAAGUGAACUUCACACUUAGAAGAAACAAAAGUGAAAGUCUGUUUUUACUCAGACACUUUAUGGGUUAUCUAAAAGGAGAGGUGUGUAGUGUAUAUUGCAUAGCCAACAUUUUAGCCAGUUUUCUUCUCACCUUAAAAAACUGUGUGUACAUAUGUGUUUUUAAAUUUUAAGUAUUUACUAUUUAAAAUUUAAGUAUUUACUAUUUAGCUAUAUUAUUUUCAAGAUUUUUAAAACUUUUAUUUUGCAGAUGGAUGUAAGUUUUUUUGUUGUUUGCAGCACCACACUACACAAAACUUUCAUGAUUUUUUGGUUCGCCUAUAGAAUUCAUUAGUCUUUGUCACAAUGUAGUAUGAUGAGGCAAGAGGCUGCCUUUCCCUUUUGAUGUGUUCUUUGCUUGAUUGCUGGAGUUUGGCCAACCCAGGGACUUAUGAGAUGUAGUAAAACUGCAGAAAGCUGCUUUUCUGAGGUUUAGGUAUUUCAGGUGAGGUGCAGUUGGCAGCAGAUGAGUUAAAUUCUGUGAUAAUUUUGGUUUUGGACAUAUAUCUUCAGCCUUUGUGCUUCAUGUUUACCAAAGUGUAGGAGCCUUAGAUCUCAGAAAUUUGAUACAUAGAUUCAAGUUCCAAAUGAGGAUACUCCACGGCGCCCCCCCCCCCCCCCCCAAUCUAUCUAACCCGAUGAACCAAGCUAGGAUUCUUUAGGGCAGUUAUUAUUGGGAGGAGUUUUGCUCCCAGGGACCAAAUUAAUUUACAGAGUGAAAUGAACAGGAUACUAUUUAAUUAAAUGUAUCCUUCUGAGUUGAAUAAAAUAUAUUGUUUCACUCUAGGGCUUAGAACAGUUCUUUACACAUAGUAGGACUCAGCAAAUAUGUGAUGAAUGAAAUAAGUGACUGGUUUCCAAAAGGAGUGUAGUACUUUGUUUCCUAACUGAAUCUUGGAAUUUAAAAAUUAUUGAGAAACAAUGAGGCUGGGCAUGGUGGCUCAUGCUUUAAUCCCAGCACUUUGGGAGGCUGAGGUGGGAGGAUCACUUGAAGCCAGGAGUUCAAAACCAGCCUGGGCAACAAAAUGACACCUGCCAGGAGUGGUGUCUCAAGCCUGUAAUCCCAGUACUUUGGGAAGGUGAGGCAGGCGGAUCACGAGGUCAGGAGUUCGAGACCAGCCUGACCAACAUGGUGAAACCCAGUCUCUACUACUAAAAAUACAAAAAUUAGCCAGGCGUGGUGGCACAUGCCUGUAAUCCCAGCUACUCAGGAGACUGAGGCAGGAGAAUCGCUUGAACUCGGGAGGCGGAGGUUGCAGUGAGCCGAGAUCGCGCCAUUGCACUCCAGCCUGGGCGACAGAGCAAGACUCCAUGUCAAAAAAACAAAAAACCAAAACAAAACAAUGAAAGCUUGAAAAACUGUGCGUGCUCAUGCUAGGAGAAUAGGCAGUGGUACUGAAAGACAGGAUGUGGGAUAGAUCUCAACCACCUUUUUGUCACCUUGGGCAAGUCAUUAAGUGCUUCUGAAGGUUCUUUCAAAGCAGUAAUAUUAGUAUGUUAACAGUAGUAUGUUAAGGCUUUAAACUUUAGCAACUUCUUUAGAUUAGAUUGUUUAAUGGUCCUAAGCAAGUGUUCUGUAUAGGGAGAAUAAAAAAGAAACAGUAUAGAAUGGAAGCAGAGGAAUCUAACAGAUCUACAGUCAACUUUCACUGAAUUCCUCCAAAGAUGAGGGUUAGGUGGGAAGGUUGUCAUAGAUUAGCCAAGUUCAAGAGUUAAAACUUGAAAAACAAUGCAGACUGGAUUCAGGGUAAAUUUCUUACUUAAAAUAACAUGUAUUUUCCAAUUUAGGAUUAUCUAAGGUUAUAAAACUAUACCAUGCAGCAUUUGAUAGUUAACAUUACUUAAAUCACUUUAAAUGUUACUUAAAGGAGGCAUUCUUUAUUAGGAAUCAGUUGAUUAUCUUAUUAUUAGUAUAAGACUUGAUUUGGGCAGAGAGGUUUCCAGCUGUUUAUUCCUUUUCUUAUUCUUUCCUUUUCACACCUACUUUUGACUUGUAGACUCACAUUGUAUCCAGUCUUUUAAAUGAAUUCACAUCAUUUCUAAUAAAUAUUCUGUUGAUUUUCUUCAAUAUUAUAUGUAUACAGUCCAUAUCCUUUACAAAUACUUAAUAUUCUGACCUCUUUCUUGUCAUUAUUUUUACCACUUAUUACUUUAAGAUGACAGAAUGCUACUACAAUUUAUGUUAGUUUCUAUUAUAUAUUGUUUCCUUAUAAUAUGGAAAUUUUCUUACAUUCCUAAGUUUUAUAAAUGUUUCAAAACUAGAUUUAGAUGUUGACUGUCAUGUCUUUUUCUUUGCAGUGAAUGAUAUUUUAUGUCAGUAACAUAAGAACCAUUUGUACAUACGAUAUAUGAAUAUUUACUAUAUAAUCCGUGUAAGGCGCUGUGCUGAGCCUUCUUACAAACUUUUUUCAUUUAAUCUUUCCAACCACCUUAUGAAGUGAGUGCUAUUUUUCUCCUUUCUUAUUGAAGCUGAAGAAACAGUAUUGGAGAACUAAAGCAACAUUUCAUCUCUAGUAUGUAUUAAGGGUUGGAUAAACUCAAAAGUCAUGUGAUACACAAGCCCCUGCUCUUAACCACAAUGUUGUAUCGUUUUGGCUGUCCUUGAAUUCCUGAUAAAACCCCAUUUGGUCAUGUUGCUUUACUAUUUUAAAUAUGUUUCUAUAUUUAAUAUAAUAAAUUUAAACCUAGAAUUUGGUAUACAAUUGGCCUUCUGUAUCCACAGGUUCUGAAUCCAUAGAUUCAACCAGCUGUGGAUUGAAAAUAUUCUGGAAAAAAAAAGCAUUGUUGCAUCUGUACUGAACAUGUACAGUCUCAUUUUGGUCAUUAUUCCCUAACAAUACAGUAUAACAACUAUUUAUGUAGCAUUUACAUUGUGUUAGGUAUUAUAAGUAAUCUAGAAAUGAUUUAAAGUAUGCUGGAGGAUGUGUGGAUGUGUAAGUUACAUGCAAGUAUUAUACCAUUUUAUAUAAGGGACUUUGACAUUCGCAGAUUUUGGCCUCUGGGGGUCCUGGAACCAGUUCUCCUUGGAUUCUUUAAUGAGAUUGCUUACAAGGUUUGGUGUGCCCAUGAGGGCUAUUAAGAUAAGGUUAGCUCAUAAAAUGAUUAGAAGGCUUUCUGUGUUUUCCUGUGCUUUUGGAAUUGUUUAGUGUAGGAUUAUGUUGAGUCAUUCAAAAUUGGUGGUGUAUGAUCUUUUUUGAUUUGAAAAAUUAGAUAGCGUUCAACUGAGGUACUUGUUACUUUGAAGAUUUGGUGAACAUGACUGUAUCAGGGCUGAGCUGCUCAUUUAGAGCAAAUUUUAGGUAAAGUUUCCAAAUUUUGCUUAUUGUCUUUUAAAUUUUCUAUCUUUUCUAGGGUCAAAUUUUAAAUUUUUUUAGUUCUAGAAAAUUCUAAAUUUCAUUUAGGUUUCUGUAUUUAUUGGUCUAAAGUUUUGUCCUAAAUCUGUGUGUGUGUGUGUGUAUGUGUGUGUGUGUGUGUGUGUAUGUAUGUACAUAUAUAUAUAUGUAUGUAGACAUGCCAUUUUUUUUAUCCCUGCUUGUUUUGUCGUCAGUAGUGUUUGCCAGAUGCUGAUCUUAUUUCCUGCUUUUUUUUUUGAGACGGGGUUUUGCUCUCUCACCCAAGCUGGAGUGCAAUGGUGCAAUCUCAGCUCACUGCAACUUCUGCCUCCCAGGUUCAAGCAAUUCUCCUGCCUCAGCCUUCUGAGUAGCUGGGACUACAGGUGUACACCACCACGCCCAGCUACUUUUUGUAAUUUUACUAGAGAGAGGGUUUCAUCGUGUUGGCCAGGCUGGUCUUAAACUCCUGACCCCGAGUGAUCAGCCUGCCUUGGGCUCCCGAAGUACUGGGCAGUUUCUCUUUGUAUUUCUAAUGGAUUCAAUCCAAACUUGUGUUUUUGUCUUUUAGAAUUUAACCAUGCACAUGUGGUGAUAACUGAUAAAUUUAAUCUUUUUAUUGUCAUCUGAUUAUCCAUUUAUUAGUCUUGUUUUCUCCAUUCAGUUUUGAUGGAUAGACCAAAUUUUCAUUGUAUCACCACCCCCACCCUUGUCUUUAACGUUUUCUUUUCAAUUUUGGCUCUUUUAAUUUUAAACAAAUAUAUUUUUAUAAUAUAAAAUUUUGAUAAUAUAAAACAUUAAUAGCUUUUUUCGGUAACAUAAAAAAUUAACUUUUUUCUCCACCCAUUUGCCCCAAAUUAGGUAAGACAUUUUAGCAUGUUUUUUCUUAUGGUAUUCCUAGUUUUGUUGGGAUAAUAUAGAAUUGUAAUUCUAGGUGAUGAAUUUUCUUAGUGUUGCAGAUGCAUUAUUAGUAGCUAGUUUUUUUUAAUUAACUAUUUAAUUUUAACUGUGUUUUUUGGUCUGUUGUAUAAUGCUUUUUGAUGGUUUGAUGCCACUCUGCUUUUUUUUUUUUUCCAGAUAAGUUAACUCUCUGUGUUACCUUGUAAGAUUUUACUCUUUGUUUUUAAGAGUUCAGAAAUUUCACUUGCGUGUGUUUAUGUAUGUAUCUUUUUAAUGGUCCUGCCUAGGAUUUUUCGUCUGAAAUCUGUGUUCUCAGGAAUUUUUCUUCCACUCUUUUCCUCAUCUUCAUUUAAAACUACAUUAUUUGGAUUUUAUACGUCACUUAUCUUUCUUCCUGGCUUCAAAUGUUUCUUCUCUCCCAUUUUGUCCUGUAUGCUGUGGUAACUUUUUAGUUUGAUUAUCUAGAUUAUUAUUUUUGUAAUGCCAGUUCUGUAUUUACUACCCUUAUAUGUGGUCAGAUAGUUUACAAAGAGUUUGUUUUUAAUAAUAUAUAUUUUUAGUUUGGUUCUGAAGUACACAUAAUUGAAUUAAUUUUGCCAAUUUUCUCAUGAUCAGCUCUUCCUGCAAAUAUAUUUUCAUUUAUUUGUUAAAUUGCUUAUUUUAAAUAAUAAACACACACGAACCCCCUAUUUAAAACAAAAGCUGGAACUUCGAUAAUAACCUAUAUCCCUUAUCCUAUCCCUUUACUUUCAUUUGAGUGUAUCAUCUUGAAUCCUCUGUUCAUCUUCCUGUUGAUUUAUUGCAUCUAUAUCAAUGGCUGAAGGUAUUUUUUUUAAUGUUAGUUGUUUUAACUUAAAAAUUUUAAGAACUUUUCCCUGCUACAAUAUCUAGAAGGUAGUCGUCUGUAUUUUUAACCAAGAGUUUUAAAGUUAUAUUUGCAACAUUUUAUACUCUUUUUCAUCUGUGCUUGAGUUUUGUAUAUGGUGCGAGGUAGGGAUACAGUUUUAUUUUCAUCAUAUACAGAUUGAAUCUCUCAUAUCCAAAAUGCUUGGGACCAGAAGUGUUUUGGAUUUUGGACUUUUUUUUUUUUCCCUUCAGAUUUUGGAAUAUUUGUAUUUUGCUUACCUGGGUUGGGUAAAUAUCCGAAAUUUGAAAAUCUGAAAUCUGAAAUAAGCCAGUGAGCAUUUCCUUUCAACAUCUUGUUGGUUCUCAGAAAAUAUGGAGUUUUCAAAUUGUGGAGCAUUUCUUAUUUCUGGCUUGGAGUUUUGGGAUGUGCAACCUGUAAAUGAUUUUAAAAAGUUCUUUUGUUAUCCUUGCUUUAUUGAAAAGUUAAUGCUCUCUUCUACUGAAUUGAUAGGCCAUCUUUGUCAUAUAUGCAAAAGUUUAAUGCAAAAUUUUUUUCCCUUUCCUUGACUUUCAUCAUUCAUUUUGUGAAUAUCAUCCUGUGUUCAUUGUUGUUGCUUUAAAAUAAUCUCUCAUACUGGAAAAGAAAGUUCUUUGCCUUUGUUCCUUUUUUUCAGAAGUAACACUUGACUUUUCCUUAGAAAUUUUAGAAUGAUCAUACCAAGCUCUCUCAAAUCCUCUGUCUUUUUGAUUAAUUUGAUUGAAUCUGUAGAUCCAUUUGGGAUUAUUAAGAUCUUUAUGAUACAGGAUGAGCAGGAUAUACUAUUUUUAUUAGGUCGUGUUUAAUAUCUCUUGUAUGGUUUAUAAUUUAACACAAAACUAUUGUACAUCUUUUGUUUCAGGUAGUUGAUAAUUUCUGAUAACUGUUAUAUGGCAGUGCUUUUAAAAAUUUGUUAUUGGUGUAUGCAAAUGCAGUGGUCUUUUGUAUGUUAAUUUUAUACCUAGCCACCUUGCUAAAUGUUUCUAAUACCUUUUCCAGAGACAAUUUUGUACUUUCUGUGUAAAAGAUCAUAUCAUUAAGGGAGGAGACCACGCCUCAUAUUGUCUUAUGCCCAAUUUCUGCCCUCAAAGAAAGAAAAAGUAAAAACUAAAAGGCAGAAAUGAAAUCCACAAGCAGACAGCCCAGGGCCACACCCUGGGCCUGGUAGUUAAAGAUCGACCCCUGACCUAAUCAGUUAUGUUAUCUAUAGAUUACAGACAUUGCACAGACACUGUGAAAAUCCCGAUACUGUUUUGUUCAGAUCUAAUUACCGGUGCAUGCAGCCCCCAGUCACAUACCCCCUGCUUGCUCAUUUGAUCAUGACCCUCUCACACGCACCCUCUUAGAGUUGUGAGCCCUUAAAAGGGACAGGAAUUGCUCACCCCGGGAGCUCGGCUCUUGAGACAGGAGUCUUGCUGAUGCCCCCAGCCGAAUAAACCCCUUCCUCCUUUAACUCGGUUCUGAGGAGUUUUGUCUGCGGCUCGUCCUGCUACAUCAUGAUUAAAAAGUUUUAUGUAUAAUUUCAGUUUUUGUGCCUGUACUUUCAUUUUUUUUCCUGUACUAGCAAAUACUUCCAAUAAAUAUUGAUUAGAAGUGAUAACAAUGAGUAUUUUUUUGUUCUUGCUGAUCUAAAAAGGCAGUUACCUACUUUUGUACCUCAUGCAUUUCUGAAAUAUUUACAUGUGUUAGUUGUGCAGAUUUACAAAGUAGGUUCUGUUUAACUAAAAGAUAUUGUAGUAUUUUCAGUCGUGAUGCUUGCAGGUAUUUUUUCUUUGGGUACUGGUGACCUUUGUUUAAGCUUUCACCCUAGGUAUCCUGGGUGUGGUGGUGGAGGGGUGCUGGUAGUUUGUCAGUCUCUUCUCUGUCAUCCUAGGAACUGUGAAGUCAGGCAGGGCACUUUUUUUUUGUAUUAGUGGCCCUCACUAAUUUCCUUCUCCAGGGGCCACUCCACAAUUGAUUUCUGCCCUGAUGUGCUUAGAGUAAGGUGUCUACAGGGUCUUUCUUCCCCUGACACUGGCAUAAUUUUACUCUCUAAUGUCAUAGAAUUGCUUUAAGCACUGACCUGCAGCAGUGGCCUGCCUUUUUCCUACAAUAUAAUCACUGAUUUUUGUUAUGUUUGAAGGACCAAAUUUGGCUUGUGAAAGUGAGUUUAGGAAUGUCACUAUAUAAUGUGAGCAAGUAGAUGAUGUGAAAGUUGAAUUUAUAAAAGGAUGAGGCCUUGCAUUUAUUUUGGCAGACUUUAAUUAAUUUCCAAGGACAUCAUCCUUGUCAUGACAUCUUGUUUUAUGUAUGUAGUAAGUAAUUUUUCAGUUUUUCUCUUUUUUGCCCCUUGAUUAACUCUGCUUCAGUACAGACCAUCUGCUUUAUUUUUAGUUUUUGGUUCUCUGAACUGCUGGAUAUUUUAAAUGCCCAGCAAUAUUUUCCUUAGUCUUGUUACUAUAGGUUUAGAUCAGUUUCGUAUAAUAUGGUUUUUAUGGACUGUCUUAAUUAUCUGUAGUGCUUGCUAAAAGUGCAGACUUCUGUGCCUCACCCUAGACGUAUUGUUUCAAGAUGUUGAGGGUUGGGCUAAAGCCUGCUUAAUAAGAAUCGCAGAUUAUUCUUCUGCACUUAAUGUUUGAGGAUCACUGGUUGAAGUUAAUUAGUAUUCUUAAAGGUAAAAGUGCCUUGAGCACUGUGUAAAUUGACUGCAGGGGUCCUUUAGGGAUUGAAUUAUCACAAUACACCAAAUUUAAUAUGGAAGCAGGGUCUUUGAACGGACAUUGUUUUUUUUUGUUUCAGGUGUUUCUCUCCAUCAGUGCAGCAACAUGUUUCCUUGUAGAGGAGCUGUCUCCUCCCUCAGGCUUUUCUGGCCAACAUCUCUAUGGAAACCCAAAGCUUCAGGUGGCUAGCACCAGCAGACGUUUUUGAAUCAACUGAGAGAAAUUACGGGGAUUAAUGACACCCAGAUACUACAGCAAGCCUUGAAGUAAUGGAAACUUGGAAUUAGCAGUGGCUUUCCUUACUGCGAAGAAUGCUAAGACCCCUCAGCAGGAGGAGACAACUUACUACCAAACAGCACUUCCUGGCAAUGAUAGAUACAUCAGUGUGGGAAGCCAAGCAGAUACAAAUGUGAUUGAUCUCACUGGAGAUGAUAAAGAUGAUCUUCAGAGAGCAAUUGCCUUGAGUUUGGCCGAAUCAAACAGGGCAUUCAGGGAGACUGGAAUAACUGAUGAGGAACAAGCCAUUAGCAGAGUUCUUGAAGCCAGCAUAGCAGAGAAUAAAGCAUGUUUGAAGAGGACACCUACAGAAGUUUGGAGGGAUUCUCGAAACCCUUAUGAUAGAAAAAGACAGGACAAAGCUCCCGUUGGGCUAAAGAAUGUUGGCAAUACUUGUUGGUUUAGUGCUGUUAUUCAGUCAUUAUUUAAUCUUUUGGAAUUUAGAAGAUUAGUUCUGAAUUACAAGCCUCCAUCAAAUGCUCAAGAUUUACCCCGAAACCAAAAGGAACAUCGGAAUUUGCCUUUUAUGCGUGAGCUGAGGUAUCUAUUUGCACUUCUUGUUGGUACCAAAAGGAAGUAUGUUGAUCCAUCAAGAGCAGUUGAAAUUCUUAAGGAUGCUUUCAAAUCAAAUGACUCACAGCAGCAAGAUGUGAGUGAGUUUACACACAAAUUAUUAGAUUGGUUAGAAGAUGCCUUCCAAAUGAAAGCUGAAGAGGAGACGGAUGAAGAGAAGCCAAAGAACCCCAUGGUAGAGUUGUUCUAUGGCAGAUUCCUGGCUGUGGGAGUACUUGAAGGUAAAAAAUUUGAAAACACUGAAAUGUUUGGUCAGUACCCACUUCAGGUCAAUGGGUUCAAAGAUCUGCAUGAGUGCCUAGAAGCUGCAAUGAUUGAAGGAGAAAUUGAGUCUUUACAUUCAGAGAAUUCAGGAAAAUCAGGCCAAGAGCAUUGGUUUACUGAAUUACCACCUGUGUUAACAUUUGAAUUGUCAAGAUUUGAAUUUAAUCAGGCAUUGGGAAGACCAGAAAAAAUUCACAACAAAUUAGAAUUUCCCCAAGUUUUAUAUUUGGACAGAUACAUGCACAGAAACAGAGAAAUAACAAGAAUUAAGAGGGAAGAGAUCAAGAGACUGAAAGAUUACCUCACGGUAUUACAACAAAGGCUAGAAAGAUAUUUAAGCUAUGGUUCCGGUCCCAAACGAUUCCCCUUGGUAGAUGUUCUUCAGUAUGCAUUGGAAUUUGCCUCAAGUAAACCUGUUUGCACUUCUCCUGUUGACGAUAUUGACGCUAGUUCCCCACCUAGUGGUUCCAUACCAUCACAGACAUUACCAAGCACAACAGAACAACAGGGAGCCCUAUCUUCAGAACUGCCAAGCACAUCACCUUCAUCAGUUGCUGCCAUUUCAUCGAGAUCAGUAAUACACAAACCAUUUACUCAGUCCCGGAUACCUCCAGAUUUGCCCAUGCAUCCGGCACCAAGGCACAUAACGGAGGAAGAACUUUCUGUGCUGGAAAGUUGUUUACAUCGCUGGAGGACAGAAAUAGAAAAUGACACCAGAGAUUUGCAGGAAAGCAUAUCCAGAAUCCAUCGAACAAUUGAAUUAAUGUACUCUGACAAAUCUAUGAUACAAGUUCCUUAUCGAUUACAUGCCGUUUUAGUUCACGAAGGCCAAGCUAAUGCUGGGCACUACUGGGCAUAUAUUUUUGAUCAUCGUGAAAGCAGAUGGAUGAAGUACAAUGAUAUUGCUGUGACAAAAUCAUCAUGGGAAGAGCUAGUGAGGGACUCUUUUGGUGGUUAUAGAAAUGCCAGUGCAUACUGUUUAAUGUACAUAAAUGAUAAGGCACAGUUCCUAAUACAAGAGGAGUUUAAUAAAGAAACUGGGCAGCCCCUUGUUGGUAUAGAAACAUUACCACCGGAUUUGAGAGAUUUUGUUGAGGAAGACAACCAACGAUUUGAAAAAGAACUAGAAGAAUGGGAUGCACAACUUGCCCAGAAAGCUUUGCAGGAAAAGCUUUUAGCGUCUCAGAAAUUGAGAGAGUCAGAGACUUCUGUGACAACAGCACAAGCAGCAGGAGACCCAGAAUAUCUAGAGCAGCCAUCAAGAAGUGAUUUCUCAAAGCACUUGAAAGAAGAAACUAUUCAAAUAAUUACCAAGGCAUCACAUGAGCAUGAAGAUAAAAGUCCUGAAACAGUUUUGCAGUCGAAACCUGAAAAUACUACAAGCCAACCACUUUCUAAUCAGCGAGUUGUAGAGGUGGCGAUCCCUCAUGUAGGGAAAUUUAUGAUUGAAUCAAAGGAGGGGGGGUAUGAUGACGAGAUCAUGAUGACACCGAACAUGCAAGGUAUUAUCAUGGCGAUAGGUAAAUCCAGGAGUGUAUAUGACAGGUGUGGCCCUGAAGCAGGGUUCUUUAAGGCAAUUAAGUUGGAAUAUGCAAGGUUGGUUAAGUUGGCCCAAGAAGACACCCCACCAGAAACCGAUUAUCGUUUACAUCAUGUAGUGGUCUACUUUAUCCAGAACCAGGCACCAAAGAAAAUUAUUGAGAAAACAUUACUAGAACAAUUUGGAGAUAGAAAUUUGAGUUUUGAUGAAAGGUGUCACAACAUAAUGAAAGUUGCUCAAGCCAAACUGGAAAUGAUAAAACCUGAAGAAGUAAACUUGGAGGAAUAUGAGGAGUGGCAUCAGGAUUAUAGGAAAUUCAGGGAAACAACUAUGUAUCUCAUAAUUGGGCUAGAAAAUUUUCAAAGAGAAAGUUAUAUAGAUUCCUUGCUGUUCCUCAUCUGUGCUUAUCAGAAUAACAAAGAACUCUUGUCUAAAGGCUUAUACAGAGGACAUGAUGAAGAAUUGAUAUCACAUUAUAGAAGAGAAUGUUUGCUAAAAUUAAAUGAGCAAGCCGCAGAACUCUUCGAAUCUGGAGAGGAUCGAGAAGUAAACAAUGGUUUGAUUAUCAUGAAUGAGUUUAUUGUCCCAUUUUUGCCAUUAUUACUGGUGGAUGAAAUGGAAGAAAAGGAUAUACUAGCUGUAGAAGAUAUGAGAAAUCGAUGGUGUUCCUACCUUGGUCAAGAAAUGGAACCACACCUCCAAGAAAAGCUGACAGAUUUUUUGCCAAAACUGCUUGAUUGUUCUAUGGAGAUUAAAAGUUUCCAUGAGCCACCGAAGUUACCUUCAUAUUCCACGCAUGAACUCUGUGAGCGAUUUGCCCGAAUCAUGUUGUCCCUCAGUCGAACUCCUGCUGAUGGAAGAUAAACUGCACACUUUCCCUGAACACACUGUAUAAACUCUUUUUAGUUCUUAACCCUUGCCUUCCUGUCACAGGGUUUGCUUGUUGCUGCUAUAGUUUUUAACUUUUUUUUAUUUUAAUAACUGCAAAAGACAAAAUGACUAUACAGACUUUAGUCAGACUGCAGACAAUAAAGCUGAAAAUCGCAUGGCGCUCAGACAUUUUAACCGGAACUGAUGUAUAAUCACAAAUCUAAUUGAUUUUAUUAUGGCAAAACUAUGCUUUUGCCACCUUCCUGUUGCAGUAUUACUUUGCUUUUAUCUUUUCUUUCUCAACAGCUUUCCAUUCAGUCUGGAUCCUUCCAUGACUACAGCCAUUUAAGUGUUCAGCACUGUGUACGAUACAUAAUAUUUGGUAGCUUGUAAAUGAAAUAAAGAAUAAAGUUUUAUUUAUGGCUACCUAUGUGUUUGUAAGCAGGUAUAUUGUAUAUUAGUGUAUUAGUAAUACUAGAUAAAUGAAUUUUGUCUGGGGAUUAAGAUUGGAUAGUUAAUAGAUUAAUACAAUCUUUUAAUUCUGCUCUAAUGCUAGCAAAUUGGAAAAUGUUUAAGUCUUUGACACUUAAAUUUAUCUAUAUUUUUAACAAAGUUCUUGAACUUAGUAUGGCACCGGAACCUGUUUUGAAUUCAGUCAGGUUUUUACUCAAGUAAGUGGUUGAUUUUUUUUAAGUCAAACUACACUGAAACUUUUAUCCUUUUCUUAGAUUAAUCUUACUUUUUAAAUGUAUUUACAAUAUACAGCAAGGUGAUUAUUUCAAGAGAAUCCCAAAGUACUUGAAUAAGGGCUAUUGUAAAAUUUAAAAGAAAUAUUUAUAUAUACACAUAUAUACACAUACACACAUGUAUAUAUAUAUUCUUCAUAAUGGAGGACAAUGUUUUGCAAUAUAUAAAUCAUUCUAUUUUUGUAAAUUGUAUAUCACUUUAAUUGAAAAUGUUCUCUACUAAUUAAUACUGUGAAACAAAAUUGAUGUUGUUUAACUAGAAGUUAUGAGUAUCUUAACUGCCUUUAUUCCUUUUCAAAAAGGAAAAAGCUGUAGAACAUUUUGUAGAUGAAACUACUGUUUAAGAUUAAUGAAUUAAUAUUGUGAAUGAAAAUCAAAAUCCAUACUUUAAAGGUAAUCAUGUUACUAACAACCUAUUUUUGAAUUCAUAAAAAUUUCUUUAUAAAUGAUGUUUUGUGAACAUAGUAAAAUAGACCAUUAUACUAUGUGUAUGUUUGAUACAGCGUCGCCAAAACUAGUGUUCUUUAUUAGUGCCUCUCACAAAAGAUCCUGGAUGGAGGAGUAAGAUGAAAUAUUAUGCUAUUAUAUGAUGCUGUUUGUAAAGGUAUUAAUGUACUAGUAAGGUGUUAAUGACAAGGAAUUAGUACUAUUCCUGUUGUAAAGUUAGAUUUUGCAUAUUGUAUCUAUCAAAAUAUGUUUGGGUUUAGAUUUUAAGUUGUCUACUGAGCAGAUUUCUGCAUUGGUUUUCCAGUCCUGUUAAAAGUUUAGAAACUUCAUAUGUGUCAUCACAGCUUUUGUAAAGAAAGUAUCCUUAAUAUUUUAUGACAUUCUACCACA